AGUGGUUGUGUACGGUCCGCAGCGGCAGGUGAAGUCUAGCAGAGGACGCGGCCAGGCGAUUCGGUGAAGCGAUUCCUGCAGGCGUUGGUUCCCCUCUUUGACCUGGUAAAUGCAGGCUUUUAUGCGAGAGGAAGCCUGGAGCCAGAGGACUUUUGGUGGCUGAGGCCUUAGCUACCUGGCUUACACAUUAAGGAGGACACAGAUUUGCUUGCUGUCUGUCUGUCAAGGCCUGGCUCAGCUAAGGACCUGUUAACAUUUCUAGAGAAGAAAACAGCAUUACCAUGUUGGUUGAAUCUGCUGAUGAGGAGCGACUACAUAUUUUGGAUUUUAACCUGUUAGCAGAUGAUUUGAAUUUGUUGAAAUGAGCAGUCGUAAAUCAAAGAGUAACAGCUUAAUUCACACAGAGUGCCUUUCACAGGUACAAAGAAUUUUACGUGAAAGAUUUUGUCGUCAGAGUCCACAUAGUAACCUAUUUGGAGUGCAAGUACAAUACAAACACUUAAGUGAGCUGCUGAAAAGAACUGCUCUCCAUGGAGAGAGUAACUCUGUCCUUAUUAUCGGACCCCGAGGAUCAGGAAAAACUAUGUUAAUAAAUCAUGCUUUGAAAGAACUCAUGGAAAUAGAAGAAGUGAGUGAAAAUGUAUUACAAGUUCACUUAAAUGGACUGCUGCAGAUCAAUGACAAAAUCGCCCUAAAGGAAAUCACAAGGCAGUUAAAUCUGGAAAAUGUAGUUGGAGAUAAAGUUUUUGGAAGCUUUGCUGAAAACCUUUCAUUUCUUCUGGAAGCUUUAAAAAAAGGUGACCGAACUAGCAGUUGCCCAGUGAUCUUCAUAUUAGAUGAAUUUGAUCUUUUUGCUCAUCAUAAAAACCAAACACUUCUCUAUAAUCUUUUUGACAUUUCUCAGUCUGCACAGACCCCAAUAGCAGUUAUUGGUCUUACAUGUAGAUUGGAUAUUUUGGAACUCUUAGAAAAAAGAGUGAAGUCAAGAUUUUCUCACCGGCAGAUACACUUAAUGAAUUCAUUUGGUUUUCCACAGUAUGUUAAAAUAUUUAAAGAACAGUUAUCUCUACCUGCAGAGUUUCCAGACAAGGUUUUUGCUGAGAAGUGGAAUGAAAAUGUUCAGUAUCUCUCAGAAGAUAGAAGUGUGCAAGAAGUACUACAGAAGCAUUUCAAUAUCAGCAAAAACCUGCGGUCAUUACACAUGCUAUUGAUGCUUGCUUUAAAUCGAGUAACAGCAUCGCACCCAUUUAUGACUGCCGUAGAUCUAAUGGAAGCAAGCCAACUGUGUAGCAUGGACUCGAAAGCAAAUAUUGUACAUGGUCUAUCAGUCUUGGAAAUCUGUCUUAUAAUAGCAAUGAAACAUUUAAAUGACAUCUAUGAGGAAGAGCCAUUUAAUUUUCAAAUGGUCUAUAAUGAGUUUCAGAAGUUUGUUCAAAGGAAAGCACAUUCCGUUUAUAAUUUUGAAAAACCUGUUGUCAUGAAGGCUUUUGAACACUUGCAGCAAUUAGAAUUAAUAAAGCCCAUGGAAAGAACUUCAGGAAAUUCACAGAGAGAGUACCAGCUGAUGAAACUGCUUUUGGAUAAUACUCAAAUUAUGAAUGCUCUGCAGAAAUAUCCCAACUGUCCUACAGAUGUGAGGCAGUGGGCAACAUCCUCACUAAGCUGGUUAUGAAUAUAACCAGUGACUUCAACUUUGGCAUUUCAUUCAUACUUCUGUAGAGAACGGAAAACUAUUGUCCAUUAACAUGAUAUGCUAAACAUUCUAUAAACAUUCUUGUAUUUAUGUGAGACUUGCCCAUCUACUGUCUUGGCUGUGUCUUGCCUUUUAAUCAUGAACAGUUACAUGAUUUAUAAUUUCACUGAUUGAGAUUACUUUGUAAGUAGCUGUUCAGAAGAAUAAAAUAUGACUGUUUUAGGGACUAGACCAUGUGCUUUUUUAACACUUAUAUAUAUAAUGGUCUAUUUGAAGAGCUCACUUCAACCUAACAGCUAGAUGUCUUUACAAACCUUAAACCAAAGGAGUAAAAAAAACAAUGGUAAGCACUGAAGUAUAAUAAGUAACCUUUGGUACAGCAGGUUUGCUGCAGUGUUUUUUUCUGUCCACAUGCAAAUUUUGGAUUCUAUCCCAGACCCAGGUUUUCUAGUUCAGAAGACUAACCAGCUUAGUCAGAAGAUGGUUCCAUGGAAGAAAAAGGCCAAGGAGUUUGAAGAUUUUUCUUCUAGACAUCUCAAAAUGUGGUACUCAUACCAUCCACAUCAGAAUCCCUUGUAGGAUUUUCUAAAAUUACAGAUUGUUGAGCCUACCAUAGGUCAAAAGGACUGGAAUUUUCCUUCUUAACAAGUAUAGUCAUGGCACCACGUAACAUUUUGGUCAAUGACAUUGUAUAAAGGGUGGUCUCAUAAGAUUAUACCAUAUUUUUACUGUACCUUUUCUAUGUCUAAAUAUACAAAUGUUUUACCAUUGUGUUACAGUUGCCUACAGUAUGAUUACAGUAACAUUCUGUACAGUGCUAUAGCUGAAGAGUAAUAGGCUAGGCUAUCUGUAUAGCCUAAGUGUGUAACAGGCUAUAUACAUAUCAUCAGGGUCUGUGUAAGUAUACUCUGUGAUGUUCAUACAGUGAUGAAAUCACCCAAAGACACAUUUCUCAGAACGUAGCCCCAUCAUGAAGUGACGUGACUACCAGAGAUUUCUGGAAAAGCACUCCCAAAAGUAAUGAGAUGUGUAUGGCAAUGUUAACUGAACCUGUUUGUAUUAAAAAGUAAAUCCCUAUGAGGAAUGUGGAAAUGUCCGUCAAAGCAUUGUCUUUUAAGUAAGUUCCAAGAUCCAUGAAUUAACAGAGGCAUAUAUUUAAAAUGAAAUUUAAUGAGCACUUAGUGACUUCAUUUGUUCAAGAAUAUUUGAUUUCCUAUUGUGUGCAUGGGAGGUUUACAAAAGACAGACUGUCCCUAUGCUUGUGCAGCUUACAAUCUAUUUAACUAUUAGAGGCCCUGUGAGAUGUAGGCAGUUAUUUACAGAUGAGAAAACUAACACAGCAGUGGCAAUGCUGGGAAUGGCCAACAGGCUUGGAAUUCAACUCAGUUUAGCACCAAAGCCAGUGCUAUUAAGACCUGAAGUUCAACAGUGGAUUCCUUACCAAAUAGUUUUUAAAGUAUGCUCUAAGGAACAAUGUUUUAAUGAAAUCUUGGAUACAAAGUGGAAUAAAAGGUUUCUGAGCAUAAAGUAGCUCUUCAGUAGUUACAACCUAUUCUUUUGCAUACAUAGCCUUUCCUUCCCUGCAAAAAGUUAAGCCUGCUAAGUAUUCAGAUCCCUGUCAUUUACUUCUCAGCAGUCUCAUUCAAGCUAAGGCUUGCAUACUCAAUCUGUGCCGUAGUCUACACAUUUUUAGGGGAUAUUUCACCAAAAUACUUGACAUGGUAACAUCACUAUUAUAUACUAGAAGCAAGAAUUUUACACUUAUGCUCUAAGUGAUCCUUUUAAAAAUUUUCUGAACUAUUUGAGGAAAGUAUUAUUUGUCUUAAAGGGUAACAGCCUCAUGAAAUGACUUGAGGAUUCCAAUUUCUUAUUAGCUUAAGAUGUCACUUAAAAGCUGACAGCCCUCAUCUGUCUCAUUGGCUACAUAAGAGCUGCAGAAGAUCCAUCAAUAACCAAGUAUAAAGAAAGAUUUUAAGACUAAGUACCAAUUGAGGUAAACAUGAAACCGUUAUAAAGCAAAUUAAAAAAAAAUACAUUAGGAAAAGUUACACAAAUGAAGUGUACGCCUAUUAUAUUCCCAAGGCAUUUUUGUGGGGAGGAACAGUGCUGCUUGUUGGCCUUUCCAUAUUCCCUCAUACAAAAAUGCUAAAAUCUAUUCGCAAGAGUUUUGAGCUAACUUCGUCUCUUAAAUUGCUUUAAUUGUCAUCAAUAAAAACAAAUAUGAAAAACCCUAGUUUAAAAAGCGGUUCAAGAAUAAUGUAAACUUAUACAUAUAGCUUAUUUUCUUCAUUUACUAGAGGAGGAAAAAUAGAACCAAAAAAUGCAUGAACUCCUGCUUUUCAAUCUGAUUACCUCAAACUGAAAAGCAGGUGAAAGGAGGAAUAUUUCAGUGUGUUUUUACAUCUGAAUCCAAGGGAUCCAAGUGGCCCAGCAGAAACGGAAUUCUUGUUAAAAUGACUGAUUCUCGUGCAUGUGAAAGGCUCUGGGGAAUGAAUACCUGUUUGGUCCAAACUUACUGUAUCAUAAUGCUGUAUAUGUUGAAAACGUAAUACCUGUUAAUGUCCUAAUGAAUCACGUUUUGCAGAAAACACCGUAAGAAACACUUCAGUCUUUCUGUAGUUUCCAUGCAUAUUUCACCAUGGUUCGCACUCUGAUCCUCAUCUGGUUUAGAAAGCAAUUCAGUUUCUUUCAAACCACCAUAACCUAAGUGCUGCCCCAUCCUUCACCUUUACCCUAGAAAAUCUGAGAAUCCAUUGGUGUGUACUGUGUGACACAAUGCCAACAAGCCUCUGGUUUCUAAUACUGGCAGGACCAACACACAUACUUUAGUGGGAAUAUAAUCUGUUUAGACGAUAAUAGAGGGAAAUGCCAUAAUUAACAAAUCUCCCUUCACUCACCACUAUCCUCAUUCUUGCAGUUGUCAAGGUGUAAGCCUCACUGUAAGUUACAAAGCUACCACUCCCCUCUUUAAGAACACAUAGCUUAGGAUUGCCUUGGCGAUGUGGGCUCUUUUUUGGUUCCAUAUGAACUUAAGUAGUUUUUUCCAAUUCUGUGAAGAAAGUCAUUGGUAGCUUGAUGGGGAUGGCAUUGAAUCUGUAAAUUACCUUGGGCAGUAUGGCCAUUUUCACAAUAUUGAUUCUUCCUACCCAAGAGCAUGGAAUGUUCUUCCAUUUGUUUGUAUCCUCUUUUAUUUCCUUGAGCAGUAGCUUGUAGUUCUCCUUGAAGAGGUCCUUCACAUCCCUUGUAAGUUGGAUUCCUAGGUAUUUUAUUCUCUUUGAAGCAAUUGUGAAUGGGAGUUCACUCAUGAUUUGGCUCUCUGUUUGUCUGUUGUUGGUGUAUAAGAAUGCUUGUGAUUUUUGUACAUUGAUUUUGUAUCCUGAGACUUUGCUGAAGUUGCUUAUCAGCUUAAGGAGAUUUUGGGCUGAGACGAUGGGGUUUUCUAGAUAUACAAUCAUGUCGUCUGCAAACGGACAAUUUGACUUCCUCUUUUCCUAAUUGAAUACCCUUUAUUUCCUUCUCCUGCCUAAUUGCCCUGGCCAGAACUUCCAACACUAUGUUGAAUACGAGUGGUGAGAGAGGGCAUCCCUGUCUUGUGCCAGUUUUCAAAGGGAAUGCUUCCAGUUUUUGCCCAUUCAGUAUGAUAUUGGCUGUGGGUUUGUCAUAGAUAGCUCUUAUUAUUUUGAAAUACACCCCAUCAAUCCCUAAUUUAUUGAGAGUUUUUAGCAUGAAGGGUUGUUGAAUUUUGUCAAAGGCUUUUUCUGCAUCUAUUGAGAUAAUCAUGUGUUUUUUGUCUUUGGCUCUGUUUAUAUGCUGGAUUACAUUCAUUGAUUUGCGUAUAUUGAACCAGCCUUGCAUCCCAGGGAUGAAGCCCACUUGAUCAUGGUGGAUAAGCUUUUUGAUGUGCUGCUGGAUUCGUUUUGCCAGUAUUUUAUCCAGUUAGAAUGGCAAUCAUUAAAAAGUCAGGAAACAACAGGUGCUGGAGAGGAUGUGGAGAAAUAGGAACACUUUCACACUGUUGGUGGGACUGUAAACUAGUUCAACCAUUGUGGAAGUCAGUGUGGCGAUUCCUCAGGGAUCUAGAACUGGAAACACCAUUUGACCCAGCCAUCCCAUUACUGGGUAUAUACCCAAAGGACUAUAAAUCAUGCUGCUAUAAAGACACAUGCACACGUAUGUUUAUUGUGGCAUUAUUCACAAUAGCAAAGACUUGGAACCAACCCAAAUGUCCAACAAUGAUAGACUGGAUUAAGAAAACGUGGCACAUAUACACCAUGGAAUACUAUGCAGCCAUAAAAAAUGAUGAGUUCAUGUCCUUUGUAGGGACAUGGAUGAAAUUGGAAAUCAUCAUUCUCAGUAAACUAUCACAAGAACAAAAAACCAAACACCGCAUAUUCUCACUCAUAGGUGGGAAUUGAACAAUGAGAUCACAUGGACACAGGAAGGGGAAUAUCACACUCUGGGGACUGUUGUGGGGUGGGGGGAUGGGGGAGGGAUAGCAUUAGGAGAUAUACCUAAUGCUAGAUGACGAGUUAGUGGGUGCAGCGCACCAGCAUGGCACAUGUAUACCUAUGUAACUAACCUGCACAAUGUGCACAUGUACCCUAAAACUUAAAGUAUAAAAAAAAAAAAAAACAUAGCUAAAGAAAAACUGCAUAUGCAAAUCAUACCGUAUUCAUUUUUUUAUUUAACUUGGGGAUGGAAUGGGGAUAGCAUACAUUUUAUUUGUACAAUAUUUAACAAUCACUUAUCCAAGGUGGGGUUUUAUGGGGAUUUUAAGCUUUCUGUUAAAUACUUGCAGAAAAAAUAGCAAGUACGAUUUGACAGUAGUACAAUAACCUGUGCCCAAAACACAAGAAAUACAGAGUAAAGCGAAAAUAACUGCUUACCAAUAUUCUGAGAGGUAACAAAUGGGAUAUGGGUUGAGACUGCAUAAAAAACGUACUGCUGGUUGAAUAUCUGAGGUAAAUGAUGUUCAAUCAAGAUGCUACUUGUAUCAUUUUGCCCAUAAAUGGAUAAAUAAUUUUAUGCAUAUCAUACCAAAUGUUCCUAAAAAGUAAUCUUUCAAAAAAGUAUAAAAGAGAAACUGGAAAGUA